AUACAGAUGUUUCAAGCCCUUAAUUACAAGCCGCGUGAGCUCUUGAGACACGGGCGCUGUCCACCUACUUCGUUGAUCCGAUGUCACAUUUUUAUUUAUUUUUGCCAUGACCUCUUUAUUAAGCCAGUUUUCUUGUUGACUUUUUCCUUGACAUUUUCAUGGCUUCACUUGUGCUUGCUUCUGUCAGCGCCAUCUCAAAUUUAUAUCUCCGUUUUCCAUCUUUUCUCCUUGCCUUACCGUUUCUGCUUAGGUGCGUUGGAUUACAUAUAUUUAGGCUUACUAAAGGUACUGCCCCCUUUUCCUUCUGUUAGGUCUUUUCCAUCUGUAUUCACGAAUGUUUUCAUCAAAAAAACCCACAAAAUUUUUUUAUUCUUCUUGUCCCUUCUAUAAUCACACCAUUUCUUUGCUUCACUUUACAGAUAACUCAAAAGAGUUAUCUCUAUUUUCUCCAAUUUCUUUCUUAUUCACCCUUGAAUGCACUCAGUCACCCUUGGCGUUUUUCAAGUUCACCAAUUAUCUCCAUGCUGCCAAAUCCAAUGGUCAGCUCAUAUUUCUCACCUUCAUUGACCUAAUAGCAGCGUUUUUUGACACAUUUGACACUUUUUCCAUCACGCUCUUUUCAAGUUCACCAGUUAUCUCCAUGUUGCCAAAUCCAAUGGUCAGCUUAUGUUUCUCACCUUCAUUGACCUAAUAGCAGCGUUUUUUUUUUUUUGACACAUUUGACACUUUUUCCAUCAUGCGCUUUCUUUACUGGGCUUCAGGACUCCCCCAGUCUCCUGAUUUUUUCCCCCUACUCUUUGGCUUUCUCUUUUUCUGGUUAUUUCUCUUAUGCCCACUUUUAAAAUUUGAGUUAGUCAGGAUUUAGUUCUUGGACCUUUUCUUUUGGACCUGUACUCUGUCACCAAGAGAGAGCAAAUCCAAAUAGAGAACGGUUUUAAAUACCACCUAUACACUGACAACAGAUUUCCAUGUAAAGCACUGACCUCUUCCUUUAUAAAAGUCCUGAAUAUUUAAUUGCUUAGUGGGCAUCUCUAUUUGUAUGUGUCAGACAGGCAACCCAAACUUAACAUGUCCAAAAUGGGGUUCCUGAUCUUCUGCCUAAAACCUGCUCUUCUCUCAGUCUUGCUCAUCUCAAUUAAUGGCAGCUCAAUUAUUUUGACUCAGGUCAGAAACUUGAAAUCAUCUUUGAUUCCUUCCUUUCUCUUACACUCCACAUUUGUUAUUUCAGUAAACCCUCUAGGUUCCACCUUCAAAAUAUAUCUUGAUUUUGACAACAUCUCACUACCUCCUCUGCUACUACCCUCUUCCUCAGUCACCAUCAUCACUGAUGUGGAUAAUUGCAUUCACUUCUUAACUGCCUCUCAAUGCUUGUCACAGCCUCCAUUUGGUCUUUUUUUCCAGCCAGGCUACUAGAGUUAGUCUGUUAAAAUAUGAGGUAGGUCAGAUCUCUCCUUUCCUUAAAACUAAUGGCUUUCCAUUUCACUCUAAAUAAAGACAAGUUUCUUACUGUGACCCUCUGGUUCACUAUUCUACUGAUUUAUUUUGUUAUGUCUCUACUAGAAUGUAGGUUUCAUGAAGGCAGGGAUUUGUAAUUGUUUCACUGCUAGAACUCUGUCACAUAGUAUGUGCUCAGUAAAUAGUGUUAGUUGAAUGAGUGUCUUGCACUUCCUAUGAUUUCAUAAUAACUUUAUUGUCAUUGAUGUAAAGAACUGAACUCAUGGUUUUUCCCUUCUAAAUAUAUUUCUUCCUCUGUGGGCUGUAUUUUUCUUGAUAGUUUCAGAUCUUUCUACUCCCUAGGCUGGGAAUUUGGACAUCAUAGUUGGUAUUUCUCUUAUACUUGUACUCUCAUAUUCAUUCCAAUGAUGAUUUUUAUUUUUAUUUUUUUUGCUGAUCCUUUUCUAUAACAGCUCUCCAGUCUGACUUCUGUUUACUAUUUCUAUUGUUACUACCAUAGUUCAGGUCCUUGUUCUUGUUUAGAGAAUUGCAACAACCUCCUUACUGGCCUUUCUGCCUUGUUUCUCCUUCAGUCCUUUUAACUCACUACAAUGAAGCUAAUUUUCCUAAUCUAAUCAUAUGAUUUUCCUAAAUCUUUUAAUUGUCCACAGAAUAAAGCCCGAAUGCUUUAACUUGGAAUGCAGAACCACUUAUAAUGUGACAUUUUCUCUAACUUUAUCUCCUAUGCAUUUCCUUAUGUGUCCUGUACAGCAGUAUAUUCCAAAAUCCCCAGUGGAUGUCUGAAAACCACAUAUAGUACCAAACUGUAUAUAUGCUAUGUUUUGUUUCAUACAUACCUAUAAUAAAGUUUAAUUUAUGAAUUAGGCACAAUAAGAGAUAAGCAGGCUGGACGUGCUGGCUCACGCCUGUAAUCCCAGCACUUUGGGAGGCUGAGGCGGGUGGAUUGCUUUAGCCCAGGAGUUUAAGACCAGCCUGGCCAACAUGGCAAAACCCCGUCUCUACAAAAAAUGUGGAAAUUAAUCAGGUGUGGUGGUGUGCACCUAGUCCCAGCUACUCGGGAGGCAGAGGCAGCAGGAUUGCUUGAGCCCCAGAGGUUGAGGCUGCAGUGAGCUGUGAUGAUGCCAUUACACUCUAGCCUGGGUGAUGGAGUGAGACCCUGUCUCAAAAAAGAAAAAAAAAAAAAAGAGAUAACAACUAAUAAAAUAGAACAAUUAUAACAAUAUACUGUAAUAAAAGUUAUGUGAAUGUGGUCUCUUUGUCUCAAAAUAUCUUACUGUACUGUACCACCCUCUUGUGAUGAAGAAAGGAUAGAGUGGGAUAGUGUGAGAUUUCACCACACUACUUUGAACGGCACAUAGUUUAAAACUUAUAAAUUGUUUAUUUCUGGAAUUUUUCAUUUAAUAUUUUCUGACUGAGGUUGACUAUUAGUAACUGAAACCUUGGAAAAUGAAACCACGGAUGGGUAAAGGGGAGCUACUGUAUUCUAACCAAGUGCUGGCCAUUAAAAACAUAAUGCGAGCCUUAAAUGUAAGCCAUAUUUGUAUGUAAUUUAAAAUUUUCUAGGACUAAUUUUUUAAUGAAGAAAAAGGUAAAAUUUAAUUAUUUUAUUUACCCUAACAAAUCUAAAAUAUUGCCAUUUCAGUAUAUAAUAAAAAAAUUAAUGGUAUUUUAUAGUGUUUUUCUUCAUACUAAAUUUUCCAACUCUGGUAUGUAUUUAUACUUAUAACACAUCUCAGUUUGGACUAGCCACAUAUCAAAUGCUCAGUAGCCAUAUUUAGCUAGCAUCUACUGUUUUAGACAGCACAGUUCAAGAAAAUAGAACUAUAUACCACUUCCUUAUGUUUGCUGUAUUUUCUGCCAUUCAGUUCUAUGUAUUCUGUAUGUAAUUGCCUUUUCCAAUAUCAUUUAAGUUUCUAUGAUCUACCAUCCCUCUGGGUCUAUCUUAGAUGCCACCUUUUUGAAAUAUGAAUGCUUCUCUGGUCUCAGCUGAAGUGAAUUCUUCUUCUGCUAUAGAAAAAUAAUGCUAAUACUUAGUGAAACUUAAUGUGUACCAGGUACUGUUCUAAGUUGUAUAUACCCUAUGAGGCAGUAUUAUUCCCAUCUUACAGAUGAGGGAUGAAGGCACAGAGAUGGAAAUAACUUGUCCAGUGCACCUAAGGAGUGGAGCCAGUGUAAACUCAAGCAGUUAUGUUCUGGUUAGCACACCCUUAACCGUUGCUAAGUAUUAUAAUAUCUCUUUGCUCUAUGUAUUUCCCCAUCCCUGCCAAACACACACUUAUUUUUUCUUUUUAUCAUUUUUAUUAUUUUUCCUCUUCUGUAGCUUACCCUGUGAUAUGGUUUAGCUCUGUCCCCAUCCAAAUCUCAUCUUGAAUUGUAGCUCCCAUAAUCCCCAUGUGUCGUGGGAGAGGAACCUGGUGGGAGGUAAUUGAAUCAUGGGGUGGGUUUUUCCCAUGCUGUUCUUGUGAUAGUGAAGAAGUCUCGUGAGAUCUGAUGGUUUUAUAAAGGGCAGGUCCCCUGCACAUGCUCUCUUGCUUCCUGCCAUGUAAGACAAGCCUUUGCCCCUCUUUCAUCUUCUGCCAUGAUUGUGAGGCCUCUCCAGCCAUGUGGAACUGUAAGUUCAUUAAACUUCUUUUCCUUUAUAAAUCACCCAGUCUCAGGUAUGUCUCUAUUAGCAGCAUGAGAACAGAUAAGUACACUCGAUAGUACCUUAAACAUAUUGGAGUGUGAUCCAUGUCCAGUCUAUCUUUAUACGCAAACAGUGUGGUAUUGUACAUGGAAGUACUGAGUAUAUUUUUUCGCGGGUAGCGACUGUCUGGGGCUGGUGUUGCGUGGUGGUAAAAAUAAUUUACCAAGACAUUUGAGGUAAAGAAAGGCAGAUUUAUUAGAGAAAGUAUGAAAAUACAUUGCAAGAAAGCUAUUGGCAAGUCAGCAAAAGAGGAGCUGAAUGCAAGUAGCAAAGGCUUGCUGGGGAUCUUAAAGGAUGGUGCUUGUGCUGUGGGCUGAAGAGAGCUUUGUGCAGUACUGAUAACACCUAGGUUGCAAUGAGCUAUCAGGCGAGGGUCUGAUGAUAGCUGGGCACAGGAAGAUUGUGAGUUAUUUGUGGAGGAGGACUGUGUGUCCUGGACCAUGAAGAAAGGUGGACUUCUAGCUUAUCUGCUUUUUUAUUUUUGCUUUACCCUGUUCCCUUAUUAGGACUGCACACAAUUUUUUUUUUUUUUUUUUUUUUUUAGUUAUACUUUAAGUUCUGGGGUACAUGUGCAGAACGUGCAGGUUUGUUACAUAGGUAUACACGUGCCAUGGUGGUUUGCCGCACCCAUCAACCCGUCAUCUACAUUAGGUAUUUCUCCUAAUGCUAUCCCUCCCCUGGCCCCCCACCCACUGACAGGCCCCAGUGUGUGAUGUUCCCCUCCCUGUGUCCAUGUGUUCUCAUUGUUCAACUCUCACUUAUGAGUGAGAACAUGUGAUGUUUGGUUUUCUGUUCUUGUGUUAGUUUGCUGAGAAUGAUGGUUUCCAGCUUCAUCCAUUUCCCUGCAAAGGAUAUGAGCUCAUCCUUUUUUAUGGCUGCAUAGUAUUCCAUGUUGUAUAUGUGUCAUAUUUUCUUUAUCCAGUCUAUCACUGGGCAUUUGGGUUGGUUCCAAGUCUUUGCUAUUAUGAAUAGUGAGGACUGCACACAUUUUUUUUUUUUAAUUGAAAAAAAAGGUUGCUCUUUAGGAGAAGGGUUUGUAUACUUGUAAUUAUUGAGACUUACUCCUGGAGUGAUCAUGUCUUGUUUGUUUCAACUGUUCUGGUUCAUACCUGUGUUUUGGCGUAAUGAUUAAUAGGUAUCUUUUCACUGUUAUAAGUGUCCAAGUUUGGAUGAUAAACUAAGUGUCCACCCUAUUGAUAACAUUUUUUCUUUUAUUCUAUAUUAAUAGUCCCCUGUUCUCAUCUGUAUUUCUCUAGACACUGAUACAUUUUUGUCAGGAAAGAUGAAAAUUUAAAACCUGAAUUUUAGAUCAUAUUAAAACUUAAUUAAAAUGCUAUAUUAAAAACUAAUAUAUGCAUUAUAUAUUUAAAUUGGAGAGGAUCAACUUCUUACUGAUUUCUAUACUGAAGUUUAAGUUCAGUGUGCUUCAGUACAUGCUAUGCAUUGACUCAAUUCUCUUGCUACUUUUUCGGUUGAGCCUUUUAUGCAGACUUUAUGUCGUAACUCAUUCAUAAUCAGAAGCAAGAACACUGAAGUAUUAUGACCGUAUUUAGUUAAAUUUGAUCAUACAGAUGUAAUGAUUAUAUGUGUUUAUUUCUACAGAAAUUCAAAUAAGAAAAAUUAAAAAAAAAAAUUUGCAGUGCUUCGGACCUCACUUUGAAAAAUACUGAUUCAGGCUGGGUGGGCUCACGCCUGUAAUCCCAGCACUUUGGGAGGCUGAGGUGGGCGGAUCACCUGAAGUCAGGAGUUUGAGACCAUCCUGGCCAACAUGGCAAAACCCUGUCUCUACUAAAAAUAGAAAAAAUAGCCAGAGGCUAAGAAUAUUGUACACAAAGAUUCUUGAUGUUCUUGAGGAAAUCCCUAAAAAUGCAGCAUAUAGAAAGUAUACAGAACAGAUUACAAAUGAGAAGCUGGCUAUGGUUAAAGCGGAACCAGAUGUUAAAAAAUUAGAAGACCAACUUCAAGGCGGUCAAUUAGAAGAGGUGAUUCUUCAGGCUGAACAUGAACUAAAUCUGGCAAGAAAAAUGAGGGAAUGGAAACUAUGGGAGCCAUUAGUGGAAGAGCCUCCUGCCGAUCAGUGGAAAUGGCCAAUAUAAUUAUUAAGUGACUUUGGUGUGUUCAUGGGAAACUGAUGUAAUUAAAUAUUCUGUUAUAUUAAGAGCGUGUUCUUAUUACUGACAUUUUGUAAUCAAGAAAAGUGAUAUAGAAAAUAUGUAGGAGACUGUUAAAAUUGGUGAUUAUGGUAAUAUGGUCAUGUGAAUCAAUUUUUGAUUUAUAAAGUACUCACACAAGUUGUUUCAAAGAUGAUAUUUCUGUGAACAGAGAGGCCAUGGGAAGAUUUGAAAAUUAUUAAAGAAAAAUUCCUACAGAUUUUCAAUGCAGAGACCAUAAUCAAAAAGUAAACUUUCUUUAGUAGUAUGUUCAAUACAUCAUUUAAUUUUUUAAGUUAUCCUGAAGAAGGAAAGGUCCUUAAUUAUUAUAGUCUAAACAAAUUUAUAGAUUACUGUUUGAAGUAAAUAAUACGAGUGAAUAUUUUCAAAUGUGAUAAAAUAGCACAAGUGGCUGGUGAUAAAAUUUGAAAUUAUGGUUAACCUCAGCUGUGAUCUUAUGUAUGUAAAGUGAAAUUUAAAUAGAUAAUUAUAGGUUGAUUACAAAAUCCAUAGUGUCAUUUUAUUUUAGUCAUUAUUGAAUUAUACCAUUUACUCUGUUUUCUUAUAGUCUUAAUUUUAUUAUAUUUUGUUGUUACUGUAUUAUAUUUGAAAACCUUCAAAUUAGAAUACAUUGUACAGUUAAAGAAAUUGACUUGGUACUUAAAAGAAAGAUUUCCCAUUGCAUACAGGUUAUUGGAGAAAUUUUCCUUUUGUUGCAUUUGUGGAAGUUAGUUUUCUGGCCCGUGGCCUUUAAUUUUCUUAAUCAACCUAAUUACAUCAGGAUAGAGGUAGAGUUUCUGUAAAAGAAGAGACAUUAAGAGUUCCUGAAAUUUAUAUCUGGCAUACGGAUAGGCUUAUAUUCAAAACAUCUUAGUCAUACGACCAUAAAUUAAAAGUGGAGUCACUAAAUAGUUUGCAGUACGUUUCUAAUAUAAGUGUAGGUGGGUAUCAAAACAAGACAAAUGCUGUUCAGGGAAAGAAGUUGGCAAGCUUAAGGUUAAACAAAAAUAAAAUUACAUGUGUUUUCGCCUUCCUAGCUCCCUGUCAUUCCUAAAUACUUGGUUAAAUUUAACGUGGUAUCUCUUUCCUUCAUAGAUAGUACUAUACUCUUGUGGGGUUUUGUGUAUACGUGUGUGUGUGUGUGUGUGUGUGUGUGUGUGUGUGUGUGUGUGUGCACGCGCAUGCGCACAUUUGCUCAGAAUGAGAAAAAAAUGGUAUUUUUCCUUCUUUCCAGUAUAUUUCUCCCCUCAUAGAGCUGUAACAUGAAUACUAAAUAAAUAUUAAAUAAGGUGGAUUCUUAGAGGUUAGAGUGCAAGAAGGCUCCUUCUGGUGGGGAAGUGUUAGAGGGGGAGUUAGAAGCCCAGGGUUUCUCAUUCUCAUGGUUCUAGUGUUGUUAACUCAAUGACUACAUUGAGGCAAGUUUGGCCUGUUUCUCAGAAUGGCCUAUUUCUAAUGCUGCAAAAGAAAUAGAAUAUGAUUUAUAACAACAUUUUCAGUUCUAAACAUUUCUUGAAUAUAUAAUAUAUUUAUUAAAACAUGAUGCUGAAGUGUGUUUGCAUGGGUACUUUCAAGGUAAUUUUCUAGCCAACCAUUAUUUUUCAGGUCCUUUGGACAACACAGAAACAAAGAUGGCUUGCUGUGUUUUUGUCAUAUUUUCAGUCCCGUAUCUGCCAUGAUUCUUGGGCAUCUUUUAUGUUUCACCAACAGUGUUACUGAACUUUUUUGCUAAAAGGGGACCUUACUGGUGUUUGCAUUAGAAAUGCUAGUUGCAGAAUAAUAGUCAUUGUAAAAAUAAUAUUAUAACAAUAAUAGCUAAUGUUUGUUGAGACUUUAAUAUGAAUGUCAGGCACUAUCAUAAGUACCUGACUAAUUUCACUCAUUAAACCUGCACUACAACCCUAAGAGUGAUACUACAAAUUAUCUUCAUUUUCCAGAUAAGAAACCAGAACCCUACGUGAGUAGUUUUCCCCUGCAAUUAUGCAACUUGGGGCCUUGGGGACACUGAAACCAAGAGAUGAUUUAAUAACAAAUCCAAGGUCACAUAGCUAGUAAGAUGUGAAGCUGAAGUUUGAACCCAGGCAGUCUGGUUCUAGAACUGAUGCUCCUGUUAUAUUAUUAUUUAUGAAUAUGCUUGGGAUGUUGUGACUUCUUCCUGUGCUGUAUGGGCUGUACCAAAUGAAACUAGAUCCUGCUCUCUUUACCUUUUCUGUCAAAAUUAUCUGUAAAGAACAAAUAUGAGCAGAAGUAGUAAACGAUUUCAUUUUCUGCAAAGAGCUGCAUAUAGGUUAUAGGCAGAUUAUGUUAAUGGGAUAGGUAUCUAAAAGGUAUUGCAAUUUGGUCAUUGGUUCUUUCUCCUGUCUCAAUUGCUCACAGAACUUUACACCUGAUCGUUUUUACUCCUUCAGUCUUUUCCCAGUUGCUUCCUAUAAACAUCCAGGUUAAGUCUCCUGAUCACUUUGCAAAUGAUUCUUUUAUUCAGAGAUCUUCAGUGUUUUGAGUGGCUACUAAACUAAUUUUAAUAAUUUUCAGAAUGGCCUAUUUCAGUUCUCCCAUGGGUUUCAUUCUAGUUAAUCAUCAUACUGCAGAUACUUCAAAAGAAAGAGAAGCUAAUCAAUUUGAGCUUUGCUAAGAAAGAAGAAAUGGCAACAAAGUUGAUGCCCCCUUUCUCCCACACUGGGACUUAGUGCAGACGAUUCCAAUUUCUUGGCAUUCUUUCCUUUGGGAUGAAAAUGGCUUAUAUUUAGGAUAACUAUAGGAUAAUUUAUCAUUCCACUUGGAAUGAUUUUGAGUGAAAAUAAUUACAUAAGGAUAACAGAUGUACACCAUGACUGUCCUGGGCAAACAAGAUAUAGGGGGGCACCCUACUGGAGUAAGGCUCAGGUCUCAAGGUUGCCAUCUUUCCCACACCAGUAGGAUCAACUAGUCUGUCAUUGGAAUAGAAUGAAUUGAUGCCAGCAGUAGUAGUCAUCAUGUGCAAUCAGGCCUCAAGUUUUAUUGUAUCCUUUCACUCUCCCUCAUUCUCCCCUCCCCCUCCUUUUCCCUCAGAAUUGGGGGAUGGAAGAAAAGAGAGCUUAUAUUUUAUUGUCAAUUUUCUAAUCACAUUCAGAGGAGCGAAGCUAAUUAAGCCAAUAACAAUGUUUAUGAAUGUAUCUUUUUUAAAAGGGAGAUGACAAUAUAUAGGAAAAUUCCCACAUGUAGGCUAAUAGCAGCUUUUUCUUUUUCCUCCCAUCCUCUAUGAUUAUGUAAACAUACAGAAGUCUAACACCCUACACAAGUGUAUUGUGGGGUAUGGGAUUAAGUACCAAAUUGCUGAACAUAUCACUAGUAUUUUGGAUUUGCUGAGUGCAGUCUUCCCAUUAAAACUAAGUGUUCAGUAGGGAGGCGUGGUGGCUCACACCUAUAAUCCCACUACUUUGGGAGGCCGAGGUGGGUGGAUCACUUGAGGUCAAAAGUUCGAGGCCAGCCUGGCCAAUAUGGUGAAACCCCGUCUCUACUAAAAACAAAAACAAAAACUAAGUGUUCAGUGAGAUUGUAGCCUAUGCUACAACAAUAGUAAUGCCAAUUGUUUUAGAGAAAAGUAAAUGAGAGGCUACCAGUUGUGUUUAGAGGAGGUCGACGUUUUAUUUUAGACAAAAUUCACAGGAAAUCACAGUGGGAAUGUGAUAAGGGGUUUGAAUGAUUGAUGGGGACAGGAAGAAUUCAUUUGAGAGACUAGAGAUGAGUCAGUAUUCUAGAUCGUGAAGUAAAAUAGUGAGUCAUGUAGUGACUUAGCAUGGGUUAUCCUUAAAUCCCAGUGUCUUAAGUGUAUUUUUUAUUCAUACUGCAUGUCUAAGGAGGGUUGGCAAGGAGUGCUCAUAGACCCACAAGGAAUCCAGGCUGAGUGUGGCACCAUCAACAUAUAUUUCCAUGACCAUAGUGGUGGUGGGGAAUUGGAACAUGGUAAAUUACACAUAGGAAUAAAAAAAAAGAAACAACCAAGGUUAAAUUUUUUUUUGACUGUGCCACAAAAUUUAUGAAUUGAACUUGCCAUGCAUCACUAAUAAUUUUCAAAUUGGUCUUUAGGUUUACAUUAGCAGCUAAUUUUUUGUGGUACACUUAAAUGUAAUUUAUGAUUGGCAUCUGUAUAUAAUUAAAUGAAAAGCAUUGCAAAGAUUUCUAUUUUGGUAUUUCUCAUGAUCUUCAAUUUUUUUUUAGGUGAAUCUAUUAGGUUUUCUAAAGAUAACUAUUUUUUUUUUUUUACAAAAUAUUGGCAUUUUAAUCUCUCUAUAACUGGAGGGUGAAUUAUUUUUCACCAGAGUAAAACAGGUCCAAAGUCCCUUAUCUAAAUUCCUAAUUUCAAAAAUCUCUGAAAACAAAGUUUUUUCAUAACUCAUUUGGCAACAAACCCCACCUGAAUUACAUGAGGCUAUUUGUGGUAUUUAUCGCACUUCAAUGUGAAUAUGAAUAUAUUUUGCCACAGAUGUAUCAAUAUAUUUGAUUCUAAACUGCUUCCUCAGACCCUCUUAAUGUGUUACAUAAUGUAAAGUAUAUGCCCAUAUUUCCUUUCAAAAAUCUGAAAAAUUGUGAAUAUCAAACACAUCUGUCUUAAAAGGUUUCAGAAAAGGGACAAUAGACCUAUAUUUCCAUUCUCUUAACAAGUUCACAAAGUGGUAUUAUGAUCCAAAUUUAAUCUAAAUAAUUUCCAAAACAAAAAUUUUCAGGUCCUUAGUUUUCUAAAUUAUUUUAAUAUUAAAAAUAUUCAUUAUUCAUUUUAACCUGUAGUAACAACAGGAGAUACUUUGAAAUGCUUGAUUUUAUCAAGCCACUAGGUGGCAUCUUUGUAAAAAUAAAAGCACAUCAAAAGAAAUGUUUAUUACAUAAAUAAAUGCUGAGAUGAAUAAAGGUAGAUGUUUCAUGAGAAAUACGAAGUCGUUUGGUGGAAUAAAUCCUGAGAAAAUGCAUAGAUUUAUCAUGAAAAGGAAAAUGGAAAAUGGUAUUGUAAAAUUACUCUUUCACUUUUGGAAUUGAGAAGCUUUUUCCUAUUGGUUGUUUUCAUUAAGUUUGAAUAUAAAUUUAUUAUGUAACCAAA